UGGCUCUGCAUCCCCAGUAAAACUGUGCCUGCAACACGUGGGAUCCAGUAAGUAGGAGAGUCCUCACAGGGAAGAAGGGAAAGAAAUUCCUAGGAUGCUGGGGUGAGGGUACCCCAGAAGAAUGACCAGGCAGCAGGCUUGAAGAGCAGCUACCCAGAUUACACAGUGGUGCAGCGGUCCAUGAAAAAAGCAGAGUUGACGGAUUAUCCAAGUUUUGGUGGAAAGUUUGGGAUAAAUUAGUACAAACCAUGGCAAUCAAGAGCUCCAGGAAAAACAGACAGGAAAUGCAUGAAAGGCUAUGUCACAGCAAUAUGCCAUGUUGCUAAGCCAUGGACAGGAUAUAAUCACAAUGAUGGAAGCCCUGAAUGCUUAUUGAACCAAAAACUGUGAUGCUAUAAUCAUAUAGAGAGGAGAGCAGAAGGAUGGGAACAGGUAAAUCUUCACUUCAUGAAAAGAAGUCAAGAGGAUCUUCUUUUUCCUUGAUGUUCUGAAGCUACAAGAUGACUUCCAAUACCAUGUUGAAUAGGAGUGGUUUUGGUAUCAGGAUGAUGCUGGCCUCAUAGAAUGAGCUGGGGAGGGGCCUUUCCUCCUCAAUUUUUUGGAAUAGUUUCAGUAGGAAUGGGACCAGCUCUUCUUUGUUCAUCUGAUAGAAUUCAGCUGUGGAUCCUUCUUGUCCUGCGCUUUAUUUUGUUGAGAGUUGCCCAAGGAAGUCAACAGGAGAGCCAGAUCAGGAAACAGCAACCAGAGGGAGAUGAUCACCUGAACCACUGCUCCAAACCAUGGGCAGUAAAUGCUGUAAAGGUGGUCCAGAUGAAGAUGCAGUAGAAAGACAGAGGCGGCAGAAGUUGCUUCUUGCACAACUGCAUCACAGAAAAAGGGUGAAGGCAGCUGGGCAGAUCCAGGCCUGGUGGCGUGGGGUCCUGGUGCGCAGGACCCUGCUGGUUGCUGCCCUCAGGGCCUGGAUGAUUCAGUGCUGGUGGAGGACGUUGGUGCAGAGACGGAUCCGUCAGCGGCGGCAGGCCCUGUUGAGGGUCUACGUCAUCCAGGAGCAGGCGACGGUCAAGCUCCAGUCCUGCAUCCGCAUGUGGCAGUGCCGGCAAUGUUACCGCCAAAUGUGCAAUGCUCUCUGCUUGUUCCAGGUCCCAGAGAGCAGCCUUGCCUUCCAGACUGAUGGCUUUUUACAGGUCCAAUAUGCAAUCCCUUCAAAGCAGCCAGAGUUCCACAUUGAAAUCCUAUCAAUCUGAAAGGCCUGGGGCAUGGAGAACAGGCUGCACUACCCUAAUAAAUGUCUGACCAGGU